CCAAACUUAGAAAAUAUUUGAAUAAAUAAAUGAAUGAAUAAAACUUCUUGGAAUGAGGUAGGAAAGAUGGUGAAGGAUGUAAAGGUUGUUCAGUGUCAGGCAGGGGAGAAAUGUUUCAGGAGCAGGGAAUAACAGGUAGAACUGAACAAGCUGUAUUCAAGGGGUCCAGGCAAGCUAGCUCAAAAGAAGACCUGUGUAAUUCAGAUGUGGGAUAGAUAGGCUGGCUGUGAUGGGAGGAUGGUUGUAGCAGUCCUUGAAAGUUUGGCUGACAUAGUAAAAGUAAAAUUCUUUAGUGCUCAUUGAGUCGUUAUAGAUACUUGGACAGGGGGGCUACAAAUUCAAGCUUUAGGAAAGCUUUUCAAAUAAGAAUCUAAUCUGGAUUGAGUUUGUAAAGCCUUGGGGCAGAAGACCAGUUAGGGAGGUACAGCAGUGGCCCAGAGAAGAGAUAAUAAAAUAGUCAAGGGAAAAUUAAGACACGAAAUCAACAGUACGGCAAUGACAAUUAAAAGUAUAAAGAAAUAGAUUGAGGAAGCAAUUAGGAAGAAACAUCAGCAAAAUUUGAGGAAACACUGGUUGUAUGCAGGGAAAAGGGGGUGUCGUUUACAGUAAUGGGGGUUUGGCAUGAGGAAAAAAAAGGCUUGGUUUUCAAGUUGGGGGCAGAUUUAAUGUAGUCAAAUUAGGUAGAUACUUAUAGAGGUAGAUAUAGUGUCAUGUAGGUGGAACAGCGUCUUAACUCAUGGUUAAACAGGGCCAGGGAAAGAGGGAGAGAAAGACCUGUGGACUAAGGCCUAACCUGGAGAACCAGCAACUCCACUCACCAAGAGGACACCUUUUCUAUUAUAAUGCAGACAACAUUUUAGCUCCUCUUUGUCCAUUCCAGAAUAAAAUCUUUACUUUUGCAUAACCAAAAGGCUCAUUAAACUGUUUUUCUCCAAACAAAAGAUCAAUUUGUCCUCAAAGGUAAAUUCUGCCUCCACUUCAGAAACAGAAAAAGUGCUGGAAGAGUGGAAUAGUAGUUUAUCCUUAGUCAGAAAGGUUUCAGGAUGUUGGGGUUCAAUUUGGUAGUGCUAAUCAAAAAUUUUAAUUUGCAUAUAAUUUGACCCUGCAGUUUCACUUCUAGGAAUCUAUGCAACAGAAAUGCUCAAACAAAUAUACAGUGCAGGCCGGGCAUGGUGGCUCAUGCCUGUAAUCCUAGCACUUUGGGAGGCUGAGGCAGGUGGAUUCCUUGAGGUCAGGAGUUCGAGACCAGCCUGGCAACAUAGUGAGACCCCCAUCUCUACAAAAAAUAAAAUAUAAAAAACAAAAAAAAACCCACAAAUACACAAUGCAGCAUUGAUUGUAAUAUUAAGAAUUGUAAACAACUUAAAUGUGUAUCAAUUGAAAUAUGACUGAAUAAAUUAUGGUCUGUCCAUAGUAUGGAAUCCUAUGCAGCUAUUAAAAUGAAGUCUGUGUACUGACAUGGAUGAUUUUUUGUUUGUUUGUUUGUUUGAGACAGAGUCUUGCUCUGUCACCCAGGCUGGAGUGCAGUGGCGCGAUCUCGGCUCACUGCAACCCUCGCCUCCCAGGUUCAAGCGAUUCUCCUGCCUCAGCCUCACUAGUAGCUGGGACUACAGGCGUGUGGCCACCACACCUGGCUGAUUUUUGUAGAGACGGGGUUUCACCAUGUUGGCCACACUGGUCUUGAACUCCUGACCUCAGAUGAGUCACCAUGCCUGGCCAACAUGGAUGAGUUUUCAUGAUGUAUCAGAAAAUGAAAAAAGCUUGCGUGUGAAUUGUGAGUACAUGUAUAUAAGCCAUAUAUGCAUGGAAGUAAGUCUGGAAGGACACAUACUAAAAAUACCAACAGUGGUAUCUUCUGGGGAGUGGGAUGGAGAAGUGAUACAGAAUUUUUAAAAAGUGUAAACUCAGCAGCUUUCUUUGCAGGCACAUAAGACUGUGGCAUCUUUAGGGCUUUCCUUUCCUGAAGGAUUUGCAAUUGUAUUACCAAGUUUUAUUUUUGAGAGCUUAUCCACUCUCUGGCCCCACCUUUCUUUUCAGAGACACUGCAGGAUCCAAUUCUGUAAGUUAAGACCAGCAGCUCCAAACUUUAUCAGAAUCACACUGAUGCUUGUUAAAAUGCAGAUUCCUGGGCCCCUGCUCAGUAGAUUCUGAUUCUGUGUAUCUGGGAUGGGGUGCCAAAUCCUGAUCUUUUAGAGGCACCCCAACUUGUCAGUGACUGGGGCAAAACCCUUCUUCGGUACUGACUUCUGAUUGUGCCCCCUCCCACUUGUUUCUCUGUGAUUAGCAACUGGGAAAAAGGAAAGAGGGCGAUGACUGGAUAUCUUUGUGGGUCACAAACAGUUGGGUUCAUCUGAAUGGGAAAAAACAAAGCAGUUUAGUAGACUUGAGAUUUUAGUGUUGCUUCUUUGAAGUGGGCCCUCUGGGUUAGAGGCUGGUCAGGUGGGCUUCCUAGGCGGUGACUUUGGCCUAGGAGAUGUCCUCCAGCAUUGGCUGCGAUGGCUGUGUUAGUGACAAAUCAGAGGGAAGGAGGGAGCUUGGCGAGUCCUGAAGUCUUAGAAUUGAGAUGCUUUUUAAGGGAAGCUUUUGUCCUGGGAAAAUGAUACCUCUAAUAUUUAAGAUGAGGUAGUAUCUAAGUCUAUUCUAAACAGUUUUUUGUUAGAAUGAUUUUUCUUUGUUGUAAAAAGUUGUUAAUCAGCCGCCUAUUGUGGGUUGUUAACAUCUCAAAAGGGUGUUUAAAAAUAAUAAACCCCAAUUGCUCCCAACAAUUAACCUUGGGAACAAAAGUAAAUGUGAAUGCUUCUUAACCACCUUUCUAAGCCCUCAGUGAAGCUGGCAGCCAUCAGUUAAAUAAACCAUUAAGUUUAUUAGUUUAAGAAUAGAAGUGUCAACUUGGACACAGUUUUCUAAUUUGCUCCUCAUUUACCCAACAAUCAUUUAUUCAAAGGCUGCUCUGCCUAGUAGACUUUAGAUAAAUCUACAAAUAAAAGCCAGAGACUGAUGGGCAGCUGGAACUCUAAGGGAAUCAUCCAAAUGGAAAAAAAAGUGAAUAAAACACAAUUUAAUAAACUUGAAAUUUUAGCAGCACAUGUAAAAACAAAAAGCGUAUGCCUUAGAGCAAUAGCUUUGUUCUCUUUCUGUAGUCUAUUUUAAGUGGGCCCUCUGGCCCAGAAUUAUCAGCCUUGGAUUAGGAGCUUUGAGGAAAUGGUGGUUUCGUGGUUGUUUUUUAAAGGAUUUUUAAAGAAAUGUAGUUACUAAGCAACUGCCAUGACCUGCUGCUAAGUUGGAGUUCAGCGGGCAAGUCGAUUCCAAAGAAGGGAAUAUAUAAACAAGUUUCAAGAAGGGGAAAACAUGGCUUAAAGAUAGAUUGGGUGUACUUUUUUGUUCACAGUUCAAUGCAUAGUUCUUUCUCUCUUUGACUUAUCUUCCCCUAAGAAAGGGCUGCCUGGUCAGAAAUCUUUGUCUCACACGGUUCUGCCCAUAGCCGGUGAGCUCAGAGGAGGGCCAGAAAGGAACAAAUGAGAAACAAUCCCCACCCAGUGUAGAGGGCCAAGCCCUGGGGUGGGGCCAGCACCCAGGCGGUCUCCAGAGGUAGACUGGCCUGCUGUUAUGCUCUAGGACAGUCCAGGGCUUAGGUUGGGGCACCUCAUUGAUAUUGAUGGCUUGCCGUGUAACCCUCAGAACAGGAACAUUGUCCAGCUGUUGUCUCUCUACCCUCCGCCACCCCACCCCCCGCAACGUUUAAUGGAAUACAGUCGCUUUGAAUCGAAGAUACAUGACUUACGAGAACAAAUGAUGAACAGCAGCAUGAGCUCUGGGUCUGGGUCCCUCCGAACAAGUGAAAAGAGGUCCUUGUAUGUCAGGGCCCUGUUUGAUUAUGAUCGGACUCGGGACAGCUGCCUGCCAAGCCAGGGGCUCAGCUUCUCUUAUGGUGACAUUCUGCAUGUCAUUAAUGCCUCUGAUGAUGAGUGGUGGCAGGCAAGGCUGGUGACCCCACACGGAGAAAGUGAGCAGAUCGGUGUGAUCCCCAGUAAGAAGAGGGUGGAAAAGAAAGAAAGAGCUCGAUUGAAAACUGUGAAGUUCCAUGCCAGGACGGGGAUGAUUGAGUCUAACAGGUCGAUCAAAACGAAACGUAAAAAGAGUUUCCGCCUCUCUCGAAAGUUUCCAUUUUACAAGAGCAAAGAAAACAUGGCCCAGGAGAGCAGCAUACAGGAACAGGGAGUGACAUCCAACACCAGUGACAGCGAAAGCAGUUCCAAAGGACAAGAGGAUGCUAUUUUGUCAUAUGAGCCAGUGACACGGCAAGAAAUUCACUAUGCAAGGCCUGUGAUCAUCCUGGGCCCAAUGAAGGACCGAGUCAAUGAUGACCUGAUCUCCGAAUUUCCACAUAAAUUUGGAUCCUGUGUGCCACAUACUACCCGGCCUCGACGUGAUAAUGAGGUGGAUGGACAAGACUACCACUUUGUGGUGUCCCGAGAACAAAUGGAGAAAGAUAUUCAGGACAACAAGUUCAUCGAGGCGGGCCAAUUUAAUGAUAACCUCUAUGGGACCAGCAUCCAGUCAGUGCGGGCAGUUGCAGAGAGGGGCAAGCACUGCAUCUUAGAUGUUUCCGGCAAUGCUAUCAAGAGACUGCAGCAAGCACAACUUUACCCCAUUGCCAUUUUCAUCAAGCCCAAGUCCAUUGAAGCCCUUAUGGAAAUGAACCGAAGGCAGACAUAUGAACAAGCAAAUAAGAUCUAUGACAAAGCCAUGAAACUGGAGCAGGAAUUUGGAGAGUACUUUACAGCCAUUGUACAGGGUGACUCACUGGAAGAGAUUUAUAACAAAAUCAAACAAAUCAUUGAGGACCAGUCUGGGCACUACAUUUGGGUCCCAUCCCCUGAAAAACUCUGAAGAAUCCCCUCCAACCAUUCUCUUGUGAACAGAAGAAAUCAAGUCCCUCUUCCCUCCUCCCUCUUCAUUCCUGUCCCCAUGGGGAGAACAAAUGCUACUGUUCUUGUCCCCUUUUUUAGAUAUGUCAAAAAAAAUUAAGUUUUCUAGUCCUGUUCUUUUUUUUUUUUUAAGUUUUUGUUUGUUUCAGUUUAUUUUUUGGGAUGAUGCCAUCUCAUUCAUCAUGUGACUGUGCCCAUUCCUGCAUGGACCUUUCCCAAGCGCUAGCACAGGUGCAAAAUCCAUCAGAGCCAUUGUUUUCAUAAAAACCAAGCAGAAGUGAAGAGAAAAGAGGAGGACUGAUGGAAAGACAGACUCUGGACAGCUGCACGGCUUGUGAAGUGAGCUAAAUGCACCACAUGAUGAGAUGCUCCUGGGCAUUUCUCCCUAUCUGUACUGCUGUCUUGCAGCUCUGAACGGUGCAACGUAAUGGCGACAGAAAGUAUCUUAUUUAUAUAUAGAUAUAUAUAUGUAAUUUAUAUAAAAUAUAUAGAAAUUAUUAUAUAUAUAUAUUAUACACUCUCAUAUAAUAUAUAUAUAUUCACACACAUUUGGGUUAGAAAAUCUAUGGAGACUUCAUCAAUGGUACUAUGUUAUUAGAGAAAUGCUUUAAUUUUCAUAUUCCAAUCAGAUGGCAUCUUCUAUCCCAGCUGGUUGGGAAGGGAUUGAAGAUGGUAGCAAGUGCUGCACUAAGGGCACUCGCAUUUGGUCAUUCUCUUGAGAGCUAGGAGGGGUCAGCCUGAGGCCGGAGAGGAAGGGCUUUUGCCUGGGGUGAGAGGGUGAGAGACUUGACCUGAAAGCAGCUGCUGCCCCUGAGGUGCAGCCAGAGUCCUGUGUGCGGACAGAGAGAAUGGCUAAUGAUGCUCCGCGUGGAAUUGCCUAUUGUUUUAUGCCACCUGAUGUGUCUGCAUGAGAGGUUUCCUUUUUGUUCCUUUUUAAGCUGCUGUUAAACCAAAACCAUGUUGUGCUACUGUGUCAGCCUUUUCAUUAUUGCAAAUUUUACUUUUACUAUUUAAGUGAAUGCAUAGAAUCCAAUUUGCCAAGGUUCUAAAGGCUUAUGAGGUCCUGAAGGAGCCAGGCCUUGUGAUGGAGUAGGUGACACAGGCCUGGUUGUCCUGUCAGCAGAAGGGAAAGCAGGGGCUGGGCUGAGAGGAGGACACGGAGGGCUCUGCUGAGGUUCCUUCCUGGGUUCCACCAACAGGGACAGGGAGUCACUUGCCUUCCAGUUCUGUGCUGGGAUGGCGGGACAGCACUUGGCUUGCUUGGCCAGCUGCGUCAUGAGUUUGAUUUGGUUUUUUUUUUUUUGCAGCUGCUUCAUAUGCUCUGCUCCAGCCCCUCCCCAACAGCUGGUAGCUUAUGGUUUCUUCAAGAGGAAAGUAGACUUUAUGCUGUACAUUUGAGCUGUAGAGCUAAGAUUCGCUUACUGGUGAGCUGUGAAACCUUGUUGCUUUUUCCCAGAGUCUGAUGGCAGUGACUGUGAUCAAGGGAAUCUUCACCGCCACAAGUGCAGGCAGCAGGUGUGGUUCAGGUCCCCCCCCACCCCACUGUGCUCCUUUGAAGCCAACGUGCCUCCCUCGCCUCCAUACUGGAGGGACGACGCAGGGGAGAACAGAGAAGUGCUUGGCCCUAGGAUUGAGGCACUUGUUUCCUAGCCCGCUGGGUUAGGGCUGGUGCAAGCGAGGCAAUGUUGAGGAUGCUUUAAGCACUACCAGCCGAAUCCGGGAACUCUGUUAACAGUUGUCCAACCAGCAGAAUGAGGCUAACUGUAUAAAGCAUGGGACCCAGGAUGAGGAUAAGGAAAGGACAGCGGCUUUCCCUGGGCAGUACAAUGGCUUGAAGGCAAAAAGGGAUAAAGUGACAGCCGACUGUGACUCUGGUGAGGAGGGGUGAGCAGGGAGGUUGAUUCUCUGAUGUUAACUAAGUGGCAAAGUCUCAACCGUGCUCAGCCCUCCCCCUCCCAGGGAAGAGAAACAAAGAUUCAAAGUAAGCAUGAUACUAGUGGGUUUACCAGUGUUUCUUCCAAGGAGACAUAUAUUUUUUAAUAAACGAUAGUUGCAAUGAACUGUGGCUCAGAGACCUUCUUAAAGUAGUUGAGAAGGGAGGGCGUGGGCAAAGCAGUGGGAAGAACAUCCCAAACUUUUGGGGGCCAGAGGGCUCUCUCCUUAGUGAUGAUCAGCUAGCCGAGCUGGGCCGUCCUGGGGAUCGGUACAGCUCCCUGGGGUGGUGACAGGCCCUUUGUGAAAGUUGUGUGCUUGGUCUUCCACCCCAGCCCCAGACACUGCUUCAAAUAGCACCAACCAGAUGGGAGUCCACAUCUGUGGUGGCAAAAUGCUGACAUUUUCCCAAGAGGUACACAAGGUGGGAGAGGCCUGCUGUAGCAGAGGUGUGUGUUAGAGAAAGCAGGGGCCUGAUUUAGUAGCAGAGAACUGGGUGAGAAAAAUGGCCAGAGAAAGUGACCUGCCAGCUACCAGUGUUUCCGAAAAUGAGGGUGGGAUGGGCCCAUUUGCAGAGCAGGACAGCAGUCAUCCCCAUAGCCCUCUGAGGAGGGGAGGGAUGCUUAGAGCAGGCAGUUCUGGCAGUUCUGACGUGGCAGGUGCCAUUGCAACUUGUGCGGAGGAGUCUUAGGAAGUGCUGUCAUAAUUCAUAAGGUCAAGAGCAACAUCUGGAUGAAUGAGCCACCUGAAAUGUGUGUGGGCUGAGCCACAGGAAGGGUGAGUCCUCUUGCUUGUGGUGCUUUAUGGUGUGCAGGUUGCUUGCUUUCCCACAUUCUCUCAUUUGCUUGAAGGCAGCCUAACAAAAGGGAGUCCCCAAAGAGCUCCAUGAGAGCUUAAGAAAAUUCAUCUCCUGAGGACAAAGAGAACAAAGAUCUGUCCUGUGGUCACACUGUUGAGGCUCUGUCUUCACAGCUGAUGUUCUCCUAGUGGAGGUACAGCUGAAGAACAUUCAGCCCCAGCACGAGAAGAUACAGAGCAACUUGGAAACCCCAAAGGGAGACACACCCUUAACACUGCCGUGCUGUGCUGUGCCGUGUCCUGAAGGAGGAGAGAGCCCUAUCUCCUCCUGGUUUUGUUGCUGACAUUGCAGCUGAUCAUGCCUUGACUCCUUCAUCUCUAACAGAGGAAGAACUGUAUUAUCAAACCUUAUGGUCUACCCAUGAAUAAAUAAAAUAUUUGUUCAAGCACAAA